ACUGCAGGGCCCGGAGGUCAAGAUGGUGGCUGUAAAACUAGGAUCCCUGACGAUUGCUUAGCAUUAAGGCCCGACAUGGAACCGGGGUGUGACGAGUUCCUGCCGCCACCGGAGUGCCCGGUUUUUGAGCCUAGCUGGGCUGAAUUCCAAGACCCGCUUGGCUACAUUGCGAAAAUAAGGCCCAUAGCAGAGAAGUCUGGCAUCUGCAAAAUCCGCCCACCCGCGGAUUGGCAGCCUCCUUUUGCAGUAGAAGUUGACAAUUUCAGAUUUACUCCUCGCGUCCAAAGGCUAAAUGAACUGGAGGCCCAAACUAGAGUGAAAUUGAACUAUUUGGAUCAGAUUGCAAAAUUCUGGGAAAUUCAAGGCUCCUCUUUAAAGAUUCCCAAUGUGGAGCGGAAGAUCUUGGACCUCUACAGCCUUAGUAAGAUUGUGAUUGAGGAAGGUGGCUAUGAAGCCAUCUGCAAGGAUCGUCGGUGGGCUCGAGUUGCCCAGCGUCUCCACUACCCACCAGGCAAAAACAUUGGCUCCCUGCUACGAUCACAUUACGAACGCAUUAUUUACCCCUAUGAAAUGUUUCAGUCUGGAGCCAACCAUGUGCAAUGUAACACACACCCGUUUGACAAUGAGGUAAAAGAUAAGGAAUACAAGCCCCACAGCAUCCCCCUUAGACAGUCUGUGCAGCCUUCAAAGUUCAGCAGCUACAGUCGACGGGCAAAAAGGCUACAGCCUGAUCCAGAGCCUACAGAGGAGGACAUUGAGAAGCAUCCAGAGCUAAAGAAGUUACAGAUAUAUGGGCCAGGUCCCAAAAUGAUGGGCUUGGGCCUUAUGGCUAAGGAUAAGGAUAAGACUGUGCAUAAGAAAGUCACAUGCCCCCCAACUGUUACGGUGAAGGAUGAGCAAAGUGGAGGUGGGAACGUGUCAUCAACAUUGCUCAAGCAGCACUUGAGCCUAGAGCCCUGCACUAAGACAACCAUGCAACUUCGAAAGAAUCACAGCAGUGCCCAGUUUAUUGACUCAUAUAUUUGCCAAGUAUGCUCCCGUGGGGAUGAAGAUGAUAAGCUUCUUUUCUGUGAUGGCUGUGAUGACAAUUACCACAUCUUCUGCUUGUUACCACCCCUUCCUGAAAUCCCCAGAGGCAUCUGGAGGUGCCCAAAAUGUAUCUUGGCGGAGUGUAAACAGCCUCCUGAAGCUUUUGGAUUUGAACAGGCUACCCAGGAGUACAGUUUGCAGAGUUUUGGUGAAAUGGCUGAUUCCUUCAAGUCCGACUACUUCAACAUGCCUGUACAUAUGGUGCCUACAGAACUUGUAGAGAAGGAAUUCUGGAGGCUGGUGAGCAGCAUUGAGGAAGACGUGACAGUUGAAUAUGGAGCUGAUAUUCAUUCCAAAGAAUUUGGCAGUGGCUUUCCUGUCAGCAAUAGCAAACAAAACUUAUCUCCUGAGGAGAAGAGACAAAGUCUCACUGUGUUGACCAGGCUGAUCUCAAGCUUCUGGGCUCAAGCAGUCCUCCCACCUUGGCCUCCCAAAGUGUUGGGAUUACAGGAGUAUGCGACCAGUGGUUGGAACCUGAAUGUGAUGCCAGUGCUAGAUCAGUCUGUUCUCUGUCACAUCAAUGCAGACAUCUCAGGCAUGAAGGUGCCCUGGCUGUACGUGGGCAUGGUUUUCUCAGCAUUUUGUUGGCAUAUUGAGGAUCACUGGAGUUACUCUAUUAACUAUCUGCAUUGGGGUGAGCCGAAGACCUGGUAUGGUGUACCCUCCCUGGCAGCAGAGCAUUUGGAGGAGGUGAUGAAGAUGCUGACACCUGAGCUGUUUGAUAGCCAGCCUGAUCUCCUACACCAGCUUGUCACUCUCAUGAAUCCCAACACUUUGAUGUCCCAUGGUGUGCCAGUUGUCCGCACAAACCAGUGUGCAGGGGAGUUUGUCAUCACUUUUCCUCGUGCUUACCACAGUGGUUUUAACCAAGGCUACAAUUUUGCUGAAGCUGUCAACUUUUGUACUGCUGACUGGCUACCUGCUGGACGCCAGUGCAUUGAACACUACCGCCGGCUCCGGCGCUAUUGUGUCUUCUCCCACGAGGAGCUCAUCUGCAAGAUGGCUGCCUUCCCAGAGACGUUGGAUCUCAAUCUAGCAGUAGCUGUGCACAAGGAGAUGUUCAUUAUGGUUCAGGAGGAGCGACGUCUACGAAAGGCCCUUUUGGAGAAGGGCGUCACGGAGGCUGAGCGAGAGGCUUUUGAGCUGCUCCCAGAUGAUGAACGCCAGUGCAUCAAGUGCAAGACCACGUGCUUCUUGUCAGCCCUGGCCUGCUACGACUGCCCAGAUGGCCUUGUAUGCCUUUCCCACAUCAAUGACCUCUGCAAGUGCUCUAGUAGCCGACAGUACCUCCGGUAUCGGUACACCUUGGAUGAGCUCCCCACCAUGCUGCAUAAACUGAAGAUUCGGGCUGAGUCUUUUGACACCUGGGCCAACAAAGUGCGAGUGGCCUUGGAGGUGGAGGAUGGCCGUAAACGCAGCUUUGAAGAGCUAAGGGCACUGGAGUCUGAGGCUCGUGAGAGGAGGUUUCCUAAUAGUGAGCUGCUUCAGCGACUGAAGAACUGCCUGAGUGAGGUGGAGGCUUGUAUUGCUCAAGUCCUGGGGCUGGUCAGUGGUCAGGUGGCCAGGAUGGACACUCCACAGCUGACCUUGACUGAACUCCGGGUCCUUCUUGAGCAGAUGGGCAGCCUGCCCUGUGCCAUGCAUCAGAUUGGGGAUGUCAAGGAUGUCCUGGAACAGGUGGAGGCCUAUCAAGCUGAGGCUCGUGAGGCUCUGGCCACACUGCCCUCUAGUCCAGGGCUAUUGCGGUCCCUGUUGGAGAGGGGGCAGCAGCUGGGUGUAGAGGUGCCUGAAGCCCAUCAGCUUCAGCAGCAGGUGGAGCAGGCGCAAUGGCUAGAUGAAGUGAAGCAGGCCCUGGCCCCUUCUGCUCACAGGGGCUCUCUGGUCAUCAUGCAGGGGCUUUUGGUUAUGGGUGCCAAGAUAGCCUCCAGCCCUUCUGUGGACAAGGCCCGGGCUGAGCUGCAAGAACUACUGACCAUUGCAGAGCGCUGGGAAGAAAAGGCUCAUUUCUGCCUGGAGGCCAGGCAGAAGCAUCCACCAGCCACAUUGGAAGCCAUAAUUCGUGAGACAGAAAACAUCCCUGUUCACCUGCCUAACAUCCAGGCUCUCAAAGAAGCUCUGACUAAGGCACAAGCUUGGAUUGCUGAUGUGGAUGAGAUCCAAAAUGGUGACCACUACCCCUGUCUAGAUGACUUGGAGGGCCUGGUGGCUGUGGGCCGGGACCUGCCUGUGGGGCUGGAAGAGCUGAGACAGCUAGAGCUGCAGGUAUUGACAGCACAUUCCUGGAGAGAGAAGGCCUCCAAGACCUUUCUCAAGAAGAAUUCUUGCUACACACUGCUUGAGGUGCUUUGCCCGUGUGCAGACGCUGGCUCAGACAGCACCAAGCGUAGCCGGUGGAUGGAGAAGGCGCUGGGGUUGUACCAGUGUGACACAGAGCUGCUGGGGCUGUCUGCACAGGACCUCAGAGACCCAGGCUCUGUGAUUGUGGCCUUCAAGGAAGGGGAACAGAAGGAGAAGGAGGGUAUCCUGCAGCUGCGUCGCACCAACUCAGCCAAGCCCAGUCCACUGGCACCAUCCCUCAUGGCCUCUUCUCCGACUUCUAUCUGUGUGUGUGGGCAGGUGCCAGCUGGGGUGGGAGUUCUGCAGUGUGACCUGUGUCAGGACUGGUUCCAUGGGCAGUGUGUGUCAGUGCCCCAUCUCCUCACCUCUCCAAAGCCCAGUCUCACUUCAUCUCCACUGCUAGCCUGGUGGGAAUGGGACACAAAAUUCCUGUGUCCACUGUGUAUGCGCUCACGACGGCCACGCCUAGAGACAAUCCUAGCCUUGCUGGUUGCCCUGCAGAGGCUGCCCGUGCGGCUGCCUGAGGGUGAGGCCCUUCAGUGUCUCACAGAGAGGGCCAUUGGCUGGCAAGACCGUGCCAGAAAGGCUCUGGCCUCUGAAGAUGUGACUGCUCUGUUGCGACAGCUGGCUGAGCUUCGCCAACAGCUACAGGCCAAACCCAGACCAGAGGAGGCCUCAGUCUACACUUCAGCCACUGCCUGUGACCCUAUCAGAGAAGGCAGUGGCAACAAUAUUUCUAAGGUCCAAGGGCUGCUGGAGAAUGGAGACAGUGUGACCAGUCCUGAGAACAUGGCUCCAGGAAAGGGCUCUGACCUGGAGCUACUGUCCUCACUGUUGCCGCAGUUGACUGGCCCUGUGUUGGAGCUGCCUGAGGCAAUCCGGGCUCCCCUGGAGGAGCUCAUGAUGGAAGGGGACCUGCUUGAGGUGACCCUGGAUGAGAACCACAGCAUCUGGCAGCUGCUGCAGGCUGGACAGCCUCCAGACCUGGACAGAAUUCGCACACUUCUGGAGCUGGAAAAAUUUGAACAUCAAGGGAGUCGGACAAGGAGCCGGGCUCUGGAGAGGCGACGGCGGCGGCAGAAGGUGGAUCAGGGUAGAAACGUUGAGAAUCUUGUUCAACAGGAGCUUCAGUCAAAAAGGGCUCGGAGCUCAGGGAUUAUGUCUCAGGUGGGCCGAGAAGAAGAACAUUAUCAGGAGAAAGCAGACCGUGAAAAUAUGUUCCUGACACCUUCCACAGACCACAGCCCUUUCUUGAAAGGAAACCAAAAUAGCUUACAACACAAGGAUUCAGGCUCUUCAGCUGCUUGUCCUUCUUUAAUGCCUUUGCUACAACUCUCCUACUCUGAUGAGCAACAGUUGUGACAGUGGCACCAAAGGUCAUUUGUGGUUGUUUUUGUUUGUUUGUUUCUUAAAUCCUACUAUCUCCUGGCCUGGACCUCAGAAGGAGCUUUUUGCUUAUCUAUAAUUUUUCACUGCCAAUUUUUGAUAUCCUCUCUCCUAGAGUUACUGUUAAAAGGUUGGUUCGUAAAGUCCACACCCCGAUGCUCAGAAGUGUCUUGCCAGCAACAUUCCUGCUAGCAUACAGGAGUGAUUUCCUAAACCAGUUUCAUUCUAGUCUGAAUAGGGACAAACAAAUCUUGAGGAAGCCCAAGUGCGUACCUUUAUUUUUGCCCCCACCACCCUCUUUCUGUACUUCAAUUUUUGUUUGUUUUUUGUUUUUUUGUCCCUGUCAUAAAAUAUUUUGGUGCUUCAAAACUUGUACCUUCAUUGUACAUCCUUUUCUUUUCUCCCCUUGGGUCUUAUUAUAAAAGAAGACAAUGUACGUUGUAAUUACCAAAAAGAAUAGGGAAAAACAAGAAUUUCAUGACUCUACCUGUGGUCUAUCUUUAAUUUCAUUUCUUUUGUUAAAAAUAAAACAAUGAGUAUGUUUGGAUACUAUGAAUAUGAUUUGAACUUCUUAAAUUGUACGAGUGAAGGACUGAGGUUAGGAAACAACAGUAGCAUGGGUCAACGUAAUUUUUAAUAGUCUUUUUCGGGGCAGUGGGGAAGGGUAAAUUUUACUUAGAAAACAUACAUGAGACUUAGGCCAAGGUUAAUGUUUUCUCAAAGGAUGUCCAGUUGACCCAGCACCAGCAAUAGAAAACUUACCUGUCCUACACUUAAUUGCUUUGUGCUUUUUAUUGAAAAUCUGUUGGCUGGACUUGCAUGUGCCAAUAUCUGAGUUAACUUGUUGCAUUGCAUCAUUUAACUAUGUGUCUGUCCCCUGUGGCCAGAUCACAAUGUCUUGGUUACAGUCGCUUUAUAAUAAGUCUUACAUCAGGGUAGACAGAUUCAUCUCACUUUUUUGUUUUUCAGAUUGUUUUAGCAAGUUAAGUCACCAGCUCUCUUUUUCAUUAUGUAGUAGCUUUUGUGUCCUAAAUCUGAUUAAGUUGCACUGACACAAGUUAUCUCCCUCAAUAUUUUCUGUUCUUUCAACUGGUGAAUACAAUAGCUAAUCUAAAUCAUUUGUUGUAAGAAUUCAGUAGGAUUGAUGUGUAAAUAUUUCAGGUAAAACCACUCUAUUAGUAUACCACUAAUUCAAUUCACGGUUCUUGUUUUGUGUGUCUCUGGGUGAUCUAAUAAUACAGACUGUAUUAUACUUCUUUUAAUCCCUUUAAAGGUGAACGCAUUCUGUCAUCCUGGAUUGAAUCUCUCGCUUUUCCACCUACUCCUUGCUGACUUGAGUCAGUGUAGAACACGUUAUUACCCAUAGCAUUUCUCAUGCCUAUAAUCAUACCUACCUUCCUUAUUGUCUACUCUUUUCACCUCUUUCUUUCUUUGAUACUGUCAUAGGGAACUAUAAUUAGCUUUCCCAGUAACAAAGCUAUGCUUGGUGAUGACCUAGUAGAGUAGAAAUUGCUUCACCUGUCCAAGUACAGUGUACUUUACCUUACCACACCAUAGGGACCAGGUAAAAUAUAUAGAAAAUCCUGAGAUAAUUUAUCUAAAUCUGAGAAUUGUCUUCGAAAUUUCUUUUUUCUCCUCUUCCAUAAAUAGGAGGAAAGUCAUGAUUCUCAAGCCAUUACAGAUUCUCUGACACUUGUUAACGGAAAAUUCUGAUGAGGCAUGAUGAGAACUUCUGCCUAUAAAAAUCUCACUAAAGUUCUGAGUCACAAAUUGUUCACAUACUUCACAGUAAGCAGGCAAUCCAAUGUCAGGACAGUUGUACACCUUUCUUAGGUUGCCUCCCCUAAUUGGGGCUGUAUUUGACAUGAGGGGCCAGUUUUGACACUUUUUAAAACCAUACACAAGGAUGCAGCACUAAGUUUUUGCACAUAGGCAAGAAUUUAUCUUGUGAUUAGAAGUUAGUUAUAUGUUCAUUAAGAAACAUGACGAAAUCUGCAGCAAAAAUUGAAUUUCAUAGGCCAUUCAGUGUUCUCUGCGAUAAUUCUAAUUCAGAAAAAAAUUGAAUCUUGGUUUAAAAAAAUUGUAAUAAAACUUUACCACUGGUAA